AUACGAGGCUGGCCAUGCCAUGUGGGAGAUGGAGUUAUUGCUCAACUCAAAUCACUCUCCACCAUCCAUCUCUAAAACUUUUUUUUUUUUUUGAGACGGAUUCUUGCUCUGUCACCCAGGCUGGAAUGCAGUAGCACAAUCUUGGCUCACUGCAACCUCCACCUCCCAGGUUCAAGUGAUUCUUCUGCCUCAGCCUGCUGAGUAGCUGGGACUAUAGGCGUGAGCCACCAUGCCCGGCUAAUUUUUGCAUUUUUAGUAGAGACGGGGUUUCACCAUAUUGGUCAGGCUAGUCUUGAACUCCUGACCUCAUAAUCUGCCCGCCUAGGCCUCCCAAAGUGCUGGGAUUACAGACCUGAGCCACCACGCCUGGCCCAUUGUCUCGCCCAUUUUAGAAUAGGGCAAGCUGAGGCUCAGAGCCAGGCAAGAGCCUGCACCCUUCAUUCUUUGUUUUGAGAAGUACUGAUCGAGCGCCCACAGCAGUGAUGAAACACGCAGAACCUCCUGCUUUGCUGAACUGGCAGCCUAUGAGAAGACGGCUAUGGGUACACAACGCCACUGACUGAUGCGGGCAAGGCCUUCUCCAUCGCCUUUGCGCUCCUGGGCGUGCCGACCACCAUGCUGCUGCUGACCGCCUCAGCCCAGCGCCUGUCACUGCUGCUGACUCACGUGCCCCUGUCUUGGCUGAGCAUGCGUUGGGGCUGGGACCCCCGGCGGGCGGCCUGCUGGCACUUGGUGGCCCUGUUGGGGGUCGUAGUGACCGUCUGCUUUCUGGUGCCGGCUGUGAUCUUUGCCCACCUCGAGGAGGCCUGGAGCUUCUUGGAUGCCUUCUACUUCUGCUUUAUCUCUCUGUCCACCAUCGGCCUGGGCGACUACGUGCCCGGGGAGGCCCCUGGCCAGCCCUACCGGGCCCUCUACAAGGUGCUGGUCACAGUCUACCUCUUCCUGGGCCUGGUGGCCAUGGUGCUGGUGCUGCAGACCUUCCGCCACGUGUCCGACCUCCACGGCCUCACGGAGCUCAUCCUGCUGCCCCCUCCGUGCCCUGCCAGUUUCAAUGCGGAUGAGGACGAUCGGGUGGACAUCCUGGGCCCCCAGCCGGAGUCGCACCAGCAACUCUCUGCCAGCUCCCACACCGACUACGCUUCCAUCCCCAGGUAGCUGGGGCAGCCUCUGCCAGGCUUGGGUGUGCCUGGCCUGGGACUGAGGGGUCCAGGCGACCAGAGCUGGCUGUACAGGAAUGUCCACGAGCACAGCAGGUGAUCUUGAGGCCUUGCCGUCCACCGUCUCUCCUUUGUUUCCCAGCAUCUGGCUGGGAUGUGAAGGGCAGCACUCCCUGUCCCCAUGUCCCGGGCUCCACUGGGCACCAACAUAACCUUGUUCUCUGUCCUUUCUCUCAUCCUCUUUACACUGUGUCUCUCUGGCUCUCUGGCAUUCUCGCUGCCUCUGUCUUUCCCUCUUGCUGUCUCUGUUUCUCAUUCUCUUUCAUGUUCCGUCUGUGUCUCUCAAUUAACCACUCGUCAACUGCUGAUUCUACUGGGCUGUGGGCUCAGACCUCAUUUCAGGCACCAGAUUGGUCGCUACACCCUGGACAAGUGACUGCCCGUCUCUGAGCCUUGAUUUCCUCAGCUGCCAAAUGGGAAGAAUAGAAGAAUUUGCCCCUAAACCCCUCCUGUGUGCUGGCCCUGUGCUAGACAGUGCUGGAGACAUAGUUGGGGGUGGAGAACUGCCCUUAUGGAGCUUGCAGUCCAGUGAGGUGGACAGACCUGUCCCCAGACAGUGAUGGCCCAAAAUGGUCAGGACUUUAAUGGAGGAGGUGAGGUGUUGAAAGCACAGGCAGAGUGGUCAGGGCUGAAGUCGGAGAAGCAUAGGGACUAGGCCCAAUCCAGCCUGGAAAGUCAGGGAGGACUUCCUAGAGGAAGGGACAUCGAACUAAGACCUGAACUAUGAGAAAUAGGCAGGAAGAAGUUGUACCUGACUCAUUUUUCUCAGGUGUCUCCAGGGAGCAGGACCCAUGGAGGGACCCCUGGUGUAGGCCUGGGCGAUAGACUCUUCCUCAGCAGCCUGGCAGGCAGGAAACAGACAUAGGACCCCAGCCCAGAUCUGAAUGGCAUGGGAGGUGCUGCCCUUAACCAUGACACCAUUGUAAGAGCUGUCCACAUUUGUAUGUUGUGCCCUGGAAUCAGCCUGGUUGAGCUCAAAUCCCAACUUAGCCACGUCUGGCCUGUGUCCUUGGGCAGUCACACUACCUCUCUGAUUUUGUUUCCUUAUCUGUAAAAUGGUGAUCAUCAUAAUACAACUUCAAAAGGAUUUCAGGCUGAGUGUGGUGGCUCACGCCUAUACACCCAGCACUUUGGAAGGCUGAGGAAGGAGGAUCGCUUGAGGCCAGGAGUUUGAGACUAGCCUAGGCAACACAGUGAGGCCUUAUCUCAACAACAACCACAAAAUCUAAAAAUUAGCUGGGUGUGGUGGUGCAUGCCUGUGAUCCUGGCUACUUCAGAGGCUGAGGUGGAAGGAUCACUUGAGGCCAGGAGUUUGAGGCUGCAGUGAGUUAUGAUGGCACUGCUGCACUCCAGCCUGCGGGACAGAGUGAGACCCUGUCUGAAAGAAAGAGAGAAAGAAAGAAAGAAAGAGAGAGAAAGAAAGAAAGAAAGAAAGGGAAAGAUGGAAGGAAGGAAGGAAAAAGAAAGAGAAAGAGAGAGAGAGAGAAAGAAAAAGAAAGAAAAGUAAGAAAGAAAAAAGAAAAAGAAAGAAAAGUAAGAAAGAAAAAAAGAAAAAGAAAGAAAGUAAGUCCUGGCUAACACGGUGAAACCCUGUCUCUACUAAAAAUACAAAAAAUUAGCCAGGCGAGGUGGCAGGCGCCUGUAGUCCCAGCUACUCGGGAGGCUGAGGCAGGAGAAUGGCGUGAACCCCGGUGGGGGCGGAGCCUGCAAUGAGCCGAGAUCGCGCCACUGCAUCCAACCUGGGUGACAGCAAGACUCCGUCUCAAAAAAAAAAAAGAAAGAAAGAAAAGAAAAGAAGGAAAGAAGCGGGGCACAGUGGCUCAGUCCUGUAAUCCCAGCACCUUGGGAAGGCCAAGGUGGGAAGAUCACUUGAGGCUAGGAGUUUGAGACAAGCCUGGCCAACAUAGCAAGACCCCAUCUCUACAAAAAUAAAAAUUUUAAAAAGGGCUGGGGCAUUUGAGCUGGGUCCCAACAGUAGACAAGUAGAAAAGGCAUGGAGAGGGCAUACCAGGUGGGAGGAGCUGUGUGCAAAGGCCUGGAGAUGGAAAAGCAUGCUGGCCACCAGCUUCUGACAAGCAGUUUAGUAUGAACGGUAUGCAGGGAAAGAGGGAAGGAGGGCAGAGGGGUGCGCACGAGCACCCGUUAGUGUCCUUAAAUGACCAGCAUGGGAACCUGGUCUCUUUCCUGAGGGCCCUAGAGAGCCAUGGAAGGGUUUAGAGUAGGAGUGGGUCAUGGUUAGGUUUGGGUUUUAGGAUGAUCCCCCUAGUUGCUCUGGAGAGGUGGAGCAGAGCGGGUACUGAGGCUGGGUGCCUGUGGGAGGCUGAGGCAGGAAUGAAGAGGGAGACGAUGGGCCUGGGCUGAGCCAUGGAAGGGAGGAGGGGUGAGUGCGGGCACACUCAGGAGCCAAGUGGACAGGCCAUAGCCCCCACAGACUGGAGGGACGCGGCUAGGGAAUGUCCCACAGAGUGGCCAGUUAUCCCUGAGAGAAAGAGCAGGUUUUAGCGGAGACGCUGAGGCUGCUUUAGAAUAUGGUGGGUGUGUGGGGCAAAAGGGACACCCAGGGGUGUAUCAAGAGGUCAUAGGGGGCAGGCCAGGUGGCUCACGCCUGUAAUCCCAGCACUUUGUGAGGCCGAGGCAGGUGGAUCACCUGAGGUCAGGAGUUCAAGACCAGCCUGGCCAACAUGGUGAAACCCCGUCUCUACUAAAAAUACAAAAAUUAGCUGGGUGUGGUGGCACAUGCCUGUAGUCCCAGCUACUUGGGAGGCUGAGACAGAAUUGCUUGAACCUGGGAGGUGGCGGCUGCAGUGGGCCGAGAUCACACCACUGUACUCCAGCCUGGGCGAAACAGAGACUCUGUCUCAAAAAAAAAAAAAAAGUCAUAGGGGCUGGGCAUAGUGGCUCUCACCUAUAAUCCUAGCAAAUCGUAGUACUUUGGGAGGCCGAGGCAGGAGGAUUGCCUGAGCCCAGGGGUUCAAGACCAGCCUCAGCAACAUAAAAUACAAAAAAUACAAAAAUUAGCUGGGUUUGGUGGUGUGCACCUGUGGUCCCAGCUACUCAGGAGGCUGAAGUGGGAGGAUCACUUGAGCCUGGGAGGUCAAGGCUGCAGUGAGCUGUGAUUGCAUCACUGUACUCCAGCUUGGGUGACAGAGCAAGACCCUGUCUCAAAAAAAAAAAAAGAAAAGAAAAAGAAAAAGAAAAAGAAAAUAUGUAUAUUGGAUAUACUAUGUGCCAGGCACGAUUCCAAGCCCCUGAUACAUUCUCUACAUUUUACAGAUGGGGGAAGGAGGUCCAGAGAUGUUAAAUACUUGCCCAAGGUCACACAGAAAGUGGAACACUGGGAUUUGAACAAGGUUUUGGUUGGGCAUCUUUUCCUAUGGGAGCUCAGAAAUAUCUGUUGUCUAGCCCUUUCUCAGCCUCCCAACCUUCUCGGUUCCUUACCUAUGUCACAGCUGACUUUGAGCUAAAGUCAUCUCGGGGCAGCUAGGUGCCUAUGUGAGCUGGCGUUCAUUUCUCACUGUUUCUCCUUCCAAAUACCUCCAGGAAGAAAAGCAAGUCCUUUUUGGUCCAAGACAUUAAAAAAGCCAGGCUCAGCGGCUCAUGCCUGUAAUCCCAACACUUGGGGAGGCUGAGGCAGGAGGAUCGCUUGAGCCCGGGAGCUGGAGACCAGCCUGGACAUGUUAACAUAGCAAGACCCCUCUACAGAAAAUGUUAAAAAUGAGCUGGGUGUGGUGGCGCACACCUGUAGUCCCAGUUACUCAGGAGGAUGAGGCAGGAGGAUCACUUGAGCCUAGGAGGUUGAGGCUGCAGUGAGCCAUGAUCACACUACUGGACUCCAGCCUGGGCCAUAGAGCAAGACCCUGUCCUAGGAGAAAAAAAAGGGCCAGGCACAGUGGCUCACGCCUGUAAUUCCAGUACUUUGGGAGGCCGAGGCGGGCGGAUCACAAGGUCAGGAGAUCAAGACCAUCCUGGCUAACACAGUGAAACCCGUCUCUACUAAAAAUACAAAAAAAUUAGCUGGGUGCGGUGGCACGCACCUGUGAUCCCAGCUACUCGGGAGGCUGAGGCAGGAGAAUCACUUGAACCCAGGAGGUGGAGGUUGCAGUGAGCCGAGAUCCCACCAUUGCACUCCAGCCUGGGAGACAGAGCGAGACUCCGUCUCAGAAAAAAAAAAAAAAGAAAAAAGUGUGUGCUAAAAAAUUCAUCAGGUACUAAAGAGUGUACGGUGGAAAGUAAGUCUUUCUCCUACACUCAGAUCAUGGAUGGAUGUCUCAGGUCUUCCCAGGCACAUUUGAUGUUAUGUACCAGCCAUAUGCAUGUGUGUGUCAUUUAUUUUUCACUCUACACAAGUAGUACCUAAUAUGGUGAGGUUGUUAUGAUUACAGACUCUGGAGGCAAAGUUCCUGGGUAUAAAUCUGAACUCUGUCACUCCCAAGCUAAGUGGCUUUGGGCAAGUGAUUUCACCUCCAUGUGCCUCAGUUUGCUAGUCUGUACAAUGGGAUGGUAAUAGCACCUACCUCAUGGACUUGAGAAGUCAGCAACUUCAUACCUCUAAAGCCCUUAGAGCUAGCAGUGUGUGGCACUCAAUAAAAUGUUGACUAAUGAUGAUUCUCA